AUUACCACCUGUUCCAAAGAGGUGGUCCAGAUGUUCAGUCUCAUUGACAGCAUUGUUCAAAAUAUUGAUCUGUGGUACUAUAUUUAUCUUUUGACCAUAUAUAAUAAUCGUGACCCAGCCCCUGUGAAUCAAUAUCGAAUUCAGAGUGCAAUGUUUACCUAUUUUAAAACAACCUUUUUUGAUACUUUUCAUGUUCAUUCAUCCACACUACUUAUUAAAGACGCACCACAUGAAUCCAACUAUGAACCUGAAAGGUAUAGCUUCUGUACACAUUUAGGCCUAUUACACAUUGGUACUCUAGGCAGACAUUAUUUAUUGGUAGCCAUCAUAAUAACCCAGACACAGAUGAGAAGUAUUGGUCUGGAGUAUGAUGAUAACUACUGCACAUGUUAGAGAAGGGCCUCCUGCAUUAUGCAGAGAUUUCCUGGGAUGACAGAUGCAUUCAGUAACUGUUCUUAUGGACAUGCACGAAAUUGUUUUAUACGUCCAGGCCGGUGUGUUUUCAAAACACUUUCUCCUGUGUAUAAUGAAACCAUGACAACGGUUCGCUGUGGAAACCUCAUAGUGGAGGGGAGGGAGGAAUGUGACUGUGGCUCCUUCAAGCAGUGUUAUGCCAGUUAUUGCUGCCAAAGUGACUGUCACUUAACACCGGGGAGCACCUGUCAUAUAGGAGAGUGCUGUACAAACUUCAGCUUCUCCCCACCAGGGACUCUCUGCAGACCUAUCCAAAAUAUAUGUGACCUUCCAGAGUACUGUCACGGGACCACCGUGACAUGCCCAGCAAACUUUUAUAUGCAAGAUGGAACCCUGUGCAUGGAAGAAGGCUACUGUUAUCAUGGGAACUGCACUGACCGCAAUGUGCUCUGCAAGGCGAUGUUUGGUGUCAGUGCUGAGGAUGCUCCUAAGGUCUGCUAUGACAUAAAUCUUGAAAGCUACCGAUUUGGACAUUGUAUUAGACAACAAACAUAUCUCAGCUACCAGGCUUGUACAGGAAUAGAUAAGUUUUGUGGAGGACUGCAGUGUACCAAUGUGACCCAUCUUCCCCAGCUGCAGGAACAUGUUUCAUUCCAUCACUCAGUGAGAGGAGGGUUUCAGUGUUUUAGACUGGAUGAACACCAUGCAACAGACAUGACUGAUGUUGGGCGUGUGAUAGAUGGCACUCCUUGUGUUCAUGGAAACUUCUGUAAUAACACCCGGUGCAAUGCAACUAUCACUUCACUGGGCUACGACUGUCGCCUUGAGAAGUGCAGUCAUAGAGGGGUCUGCAACAACAGAAGGAACUGCCAUUGCCAUAUAGGCUGGGAUCCUCCACUGUGCCUAAGAAGAGGUGCUGGUGGGAGUGUCGACAGCGGGCCACCUCCAAAAAGAACAUGUUCUCUCAGACAAAGCCAACAAUCAGAGAUGUAUCUGAGAGUGGUCUUUGGUCGUAUUUACGCCUUCAUAAUUGCACUGCUCUUUGGGACAGCCACAAAUGUGCAAACUUAUCAGGACCACCACCGGUUAGGAAGAGACAGUUACUAA